UCGGCGUCUCCCCGCUCCCACGUCGCCGCCGGGUCCCGUUGCUCUGUCCCUGCGGUUAGGACUGCGGGGGGGCGGGGCAGAGGCCUUGACACGCAUCUUACCCACCCCCUUCCAGAAGAGAUGAAGGGGCUCCCAGCGCCGUUCCUUUUUUUCUUGGAAUGUCAGCAGAGCUUGUGUUUGGCGAUAAGCUAGCCUUGCCCGUCUGGCUAUAAAUAGCACAGAUGGACGGCCCACUCGUGCCCCAGCCCAGCUGUGUGACCCCAGGGUGCUUCAUGGGCCGGGGAGGUGGCCUUCAGUGCAGCUCCUUCCAGGUGACAAAGUCUUCCCACGUGCAGGCCACUCAGUCCCUCCCCAGCCCCAGCGAGUGGACAGGUCGGUUUAGCCUCUGGUUAGGAGCUGCUCAUGGCCAGUGAGCAGGGCUGGGUCCAGGCGGCGUUUGAGGACUGGCUGGGGCUGACAGGGUCACACACCCUGGGAGAAGGACAGUGUCUGUGGUCGCCAGACCCACUUACCCUGCCCAGACUCCCAAUCUGUCUCUUCCUAACUUUGGGGACAAUUAUGUGCCUCAGUUUCCCCUCAUGUUGAGGUGCACAGUGCUGUUGGGUUCCCCAGGCUCUGGUCAUCCGUUCAUGGUUUUUAGUUUCUGGCAUCAUUCUGAGACUCGGCAGUUGCUUCUCACUGCUGCGGCCGGGCCUGUCUGUGGGAGCUGCAUCCUCCUCAUCUGCAGGCGCUGGAAAACCAGACACGAUCGGACAUGCAUGUGGUUCUGCGGCCAAAGCACGCCCUUUGGUUGUGAACUUCAUGAUACCUGUGUGCAGCUCUGUCAUUUCCACUCUGCUCUGCUGCACAGCAGGCAGAAGCCCUGGCCGUCCCCUGCUGUGUUCUUCAGGAGAAACGUCAGGGGCCUUCCUCCAAGGUUCUCCAGCCCCACACCCCUGUGGAGGAAGGUGCUCUCCACCGCGGUAGUGGGGGCGCCCCUGCUCCUCGGAGCCCGCUAUGUCAUGGCAGAGGCACGGGAGAAGAGGAGGAUGCGGCUCGUGGUGGAUGGCAUGGGGCGCUUUGGCAGGUCUCUGAAGGUCGGCCUGCAGAUCUCCCUGGACUACUGGUGGUGCACCAAUGUUGUCCUUCGAGGGGUGGAAGAGAACAGCCCAGGCUACUUGGAGGUGAUGUCUGCGUGUCACCAGCGGGCGGCUGAUGCCCUGGUGGCAGGGGCCAUCAGCAACGGGGGCCUCUACGUGAAGCUGGGCCAGGGGCUGUGCUCCUUCAACCACCUGCUUCCCCCCGAGUAUACCCGGACCCUGCGCGUGCUAGAGGACAGGGCCCUCAAGCGGGGCUUCCAGGAGGUGGAUGAGUUGUUCCUUGAGGACUUCCAGGCCCUCCCCCACGAGCUCUUCCAGGAGUUUGACUACCAGCCAAUUGCUGCCGCCAGCCUGGCACAGGUGCACAGAGCCAAGCUGCACGAUGGCACCAGCGUGGCUGUGAAGGUGCAGUACAUCGACCUGCGGGACCGCUUUGAUGGGGACAUCCACACCCUGGAGCUCCUGCUGCGGCUCGUUGAGGUCAUGCACCCCAGCUUUGGCUUCAGCUGGGUCCUCCAGGACCUGAAGGGGACCCUGGCCCAGGAGCUGGACUUCGAGAAUGAGGGCCGCAACGCAGAGCGCUGUGCGCGGGAGCUGGCGCACUUCCCCUACGUCGUGGUGCCCCGCGUGCACUGGGACAAGUCCAGCAAGCGCGUGCUCACUGCCGACUUCUGCGCCGGCUGCAAGGUCAACGAUGUGGAGGCCAUCAGGAGCCAGGGGCUGGCAGUGCAUGACAUAGCAGAAAAGCUCAUCAAGGCCUUUGCUGAGCAGAUAUUUUACACCGGCUUCAUCCACUCGGACCCACAUCCUGGCAACGUUCUGGUGCGGAAAGGCCCGGACGGGAAAGCGGAGCUGGUGCUGCUGGACCACGGGCUCUACCAGUUCCUGGAGGAGAAGGACCGCGCAGCCCUCUGCCAGCUGUGGCGGGCCAUCAUCCUGCGGGACGACGCCGCCAUGAGGGCGCACGCAGCCGCACUGGGGGUGCAAGACUACCUCCUGUUCGCCGAGAUGCUCAUGCAGCGCCCCGUGCGCCUGGGGCAGCUGUGGGGCUCGCACCUACUGAGCCGCGAAGAGGCGGCCUACAUGGUGGACAUGGCCCGCGAGCGCUUCGAGGCCGUCAUGGCGGUGCUCAGGGAGCUGCCGCGGCCCAUGCUGCUGGUGCUGCGCAACAUCAACACCGUGCGCGCUAUCAACGUGGCCCUCGGCGCCCCCGUGGACCGCUACUUCCUUAUGGCUAAAAGGGCUGUCCGGGGCUGGAGCCGCCUGGCGGGCGCCACGUAUCGGGGUGUCUACGGCACCAGCCUCCUGCGCCACGCCAAGGUCGUCUGGGAGAUGCUCAAGUUUGAAGUGGCGCUCAGGCUGGAGACCUUGGCCAUGCGGCUGACCGCCCUCCUGGCUCGUGCUCUGGUCCACCUGAGCCUCGUGCCCCCAGCGGAGGAGCUCUACCAGUACCUGGAGACCUAGGGUGCAGCCGCCCAGGGCCGGCGGGGCCCUUUUCACCUUGGGCUGACGGAGGUGGCGGGGCUAGAGGUGUAGACACCCCGAGCCCCGUGGGCACUCGCACUGGGGGGCUGUGACAGCAGCUGGGCCAGGAGGCCGUGUAAUGACCACACACUCCUCUCAAGCAAAAAA